UGUCGGUCUCUCCGGGAAUCCUUGCCACUGUCUCCAGCAGGGAUUCUAAAUUCGGGUUUGGGAACUCCCCAAAUUGUCCAGCUAUCAUUCAUCGUAGUGUUAGUACGGGGUCACUGAACACUUUACCAAGUUGCCAAAAUUGAUUUGGCAUGCAUUUUGUUUUGUUUUAGGUACUACGUAAAAUGGCACAUUUUUGUUUUUUAUUUUUGAGACAAGAUCUCACUUCUUCCCCCAGGCUGGAGUACAGUGGCACGAUCACGGCUCACUGCAGCCUCGAAUCCUGGGCUCGAGAGAUCCUUCCGCCUCAGCCUUCCAAUGAGCUAGGGCUACAGACAUGCACCACCAAGCCCGGCUAAUUUUUUUUUUUUUAAUUUUUUGUAGGGGCAGGGGUCUCGCUAUGUUGUCCAGACUGGUAUUGAACUCCUGGGCUCAGGCGAUCUUCCUGCCUCAGCCUCGCAAAGUGCUGGGAUUAUAGGGGUGAUCCCCCGCCCUCGGCCAAAUGGCACACGCUUUGAUGGAAGAGUUUAAAGAACGCUGUACUCAGUGUGCUGCUGUCUCAUGGGGUCUUACUGAUGAAGGCAAAUAUUAUUGCACUUCUUGCCACAAUGUUACAGAGAGAUAUCAGGAAGUUACAAACACUGAUCUUAUUCCUAAUACCCAAAUAAAAGCCCUCAACCGGGGGCUUAAAAAAAAAAACAAUACUGAAAAAGGCUGGGAUUGGUAUGUGUGUGAAGGUUUCCAGUAUAUUCUUUAUCAACAAGCAGAAGCCUUAAAGAACCUUGGAGUAGGCCCAGAGUUAAAGAACGAUGUUUUACAUAAUUUUUGGAAGCGCUACCUUCAGAAGAGCAAGCAGGCAUAUUGUAAGAACCCAGUUUAUACCACUGGAAGGAAACCUACGGUAUUAGAAGAUAAUCUAAGUCAUUCAGACUGGGCUAGUGAGCCUGAGCUGCUAAGUGAUGUCAGCUGUCCUCCUUUUCUUGAAAGUGGAGCGGAGUCUCAGUCUGACAUCCACACUCGAAAACCUUUCCCCGUCAGCAAAGCAUCACAAUCAGAAACGUCUGUCUGCUCUGGAUCUCUGGAUGGAGUUGAAUACUCACAACGAAAGGAGAAGGGAAUCGUGAAGAUGACCAUGCCACAGACACUUGCCUUCUGUUAUCUGUCCUUACUUUGGCAGAGAGAAGCAAUAACACUUUCAGAUCUUUUGAGGUUUGUUGAAGAGGACCAUAUUCCUUACAUAAAUGCUUUUCAGCAUUUUCCAGAACAGAUGAAAUUAUAUGGACGUGACAGAGGAAUCUUUGGUAUAGAGUCUUGGCCUGACUACGAGGACAUCUACAAAAAAACAGUAGAAGUUGGAACAUUUUUAGAUUUGCCUCGUUUUCCAGACAUAACUGAAGACUGCUAUCUUCAUCCCAACAUACUGUGUAUGAAAUACUUGAUGGAAGUCAACCUCCCUGAUGAAAUGCAUAGCUUAACUUGCCACGUGGUAAAAAUGACUGGAAUGGGAGAAGUGGAUUUUCUGACAUUUGAUCCUAUAGCUAAAAUGGCAAAAACUGUUAAGUACGAUGUACAAGCUGUAGCUAUCAUUGUGGUGGUAUUGAAACUGCUCUUUCUAUUGGAUGACAGUUUCGAGUGGUCUUUGUCUAAUCUUGCUGAAAAGCAUAAUGAAAAGAACAAAAAAGAUAAGCCAUGGUUUGAUUUCAGAAAGUGGUACCAAAUUAUGAAGAAAGCUUUUGAUGAGAAAAAACAAAAAUGGGAAGAAGCAAGGGCCAAGUACCUGUGGAAAAGUGAAAAGCCACUCUACUACUCAUUUGUCGACAAACCAGUAGCAUAUAAAAAAAGAGAAAUGGUGGUGAAUCUACAGAAACAAUUUAGCACACUGGUCGAGUCAACAGCAACUGCUGGAAAAAAAAGCCCUUCAAGUUUUCAGUUCAACUGGACUGAAGAGGACACUGAUAGAACGUGUUUCCAUGGACACAGCCUUCAGGGAGUCCUGAAAGAGAAAGGCCAAUCACUGCUGACUAAGAAUUCAUUAUAUUGGCUUAGUACACAGAAAUUCUGCAGAUGCUAUUGUACACAUGUGACAACCUAUGAAGAAUCAAAUUAUUCUCUGAGUUAUCAGUUUAUACUAAAUCUCUUCUCCUUCCUGCUCAGAAUAAAGACUUCCCUUCUCCAUGAAGAAGUGAGCUUAGUUGAGAAGAAACUUUUUGAGAAAAAAUACAGUGUAAAAAGAAAGAAAUCAAGAUCCAAGAAAGUGAGACGACAUUGAGAAAAUGAAAUAGAAACUUUCUGGAAAAAUAUUUUAAUAGUGAUAAUAACAUCAGAUUUUAAUAUAACAUUCCAGAGAAUUGUGGAAAAUACUGCAUAUAUAUGUAUAGACUCUGACACAUAUUUACAUAUAUAUCAAGUGUGCUUAGAAAAAUGUAUAUUGUAAAGCAGGUGAGCUUCAUUUGAUUUUAUUUUUCAGAGUAUGAACAUUCUAAGAGAAAGUUAAAACAAUAGCAAAUUGUAUAAUUGUAUCCAGAAAUGUAUACUCAUCGUAUUUUAAAGCUAAAUUUAUUUUUUAAACUAGAUCCCUUCAUUAUUCUUUAUGCCCCAGAGUAAAUCCCAGAUGGAUCAAAGAUCUAAACAUAAUCUUUCAUAUGUAAAAAUAUAAAAGUAUUAGUAGAAAACAAAUAUGAAUGCUUUGAUGAUCUUGGAA